AGUGAAGCUUGUUUGUUGAUCCUGUAUUCUCAUCCAGAGGAAGUAGAUCUUUGAGAAUGUCUAAGGAAGGGUAAGUGAUUUUAUUAUUCUUUCUCUUUCAUUUUUCUCAGUGAAGAGGUAUCAUCUGCAUGAAUUAAAAGAUUAAUAAGCAGUGCUACCAGUCCGAGAGUGGAGGUAGAGGCAGAGAUUGAAAGAAAUUCAGCCCAAAUCUUAUAGUGUUUCAUGUGUAAUCUACUAUAAAGUUGCUAUUGUUGUUUUGAAAGACAGCACUGAGUAAGGGCAAUCUUAAUAGGAAUUUUGUAAGAUAUAAGUACUUUGUUUACUCUGUGGUAAAUUCAUUUUGUUUUUCUGCAGAAUGUAUUUAUCAAGAUUGGAAGCAAACGGUGGUUUACCGAAGAAUUGAGGGAAGCUUAAAAAUUCAAUGGCGUUUUAAAAUAAGUUGUACCUUUAGAAAAUGGUGUGAAAUAUUUAGUGAAAAACAGCCUAUGAUUUUGUUUCUGGGGCAUGUAGGCAAAAAAUAAUUUAGAGUAGAAUUCCCUAUUCUAAUUUGCUUUGCAAUAUAAGAUAGUUCCAUAUUAUUUUUGUAUUAUUUUCUCUUAUGCUUCAGAGUCUGAAUUAUUACUGAUUCUCUUUUUGUGACCACUAUAAUAAGUGAUAAGUUAAUAACUGCAUACUGUUGGUUAUUUCAUUUCUAGCCUUCAGGCAUAACUAGACCUGGUUAAUUUUAGAGAGAUGUUUCUUUUAAUAAAAUAGGACAUAAAUCUCUCAAAAAAAUUCUUUAAAAAUACAGUAAAAGUUUAGUUUUUAUUUUUCUGGAAUCUAUUAAUUAUCUUUCUAGUUCUUUUGUUCUGUAAGAAAAUUUGAAGUGGUUCCAGAGCCUCACAUUUACAACUUAUUUUAAUCUAAUCAUGUAUUGAUUAUGAACAAAAUAAAAUUGGCCCACUUUACUGCUAUUUUUAGAUUUCAUUAUUGAAUAACGAGAACAACCAGGGGUAUAAGUAAUUCUGUAUUAUUUUUAGACCUUUUAUGACAUCACUAGAAAUUUGAGGUUUCUUUUAAAUGUGAAAAUUAUGAAAGGACUGCUGUUUUAGAUUGGUAUAUUUUCUUAAAGGACUGCCUUUUUAGGUUGGUAUAUUUUCUUUCCUUCUACCACUGGCUAUAGAUAGGUAGGUGUUAAACCAUUUUUAUGAUAAGGACUAUCACAGGUGCUAGUAUGUUUGUCAAUCUUGUACACAGGGUUGUUUAUAAAGCUAUUAUAGUUUGUAGAUUUAAGAUGAAUUGUAUUUCUAGACGCGGUUAAAGUUCUUGGAAGUAGUUAGUGCUAAUUUUUACCCUAUGGUAAAGUAUAUGUUAGACUUGGUUAGUUAGAGAAAGUUGGAGGGACCUAUAUUACCCCUCUAGGACACUGUAACGGCAGAUUUUUUUUUUAGGUUUAUCUCUAGGAGCCUCUGGAGCAAUGUCUGUACUGUCCGAAUGGAUAAUAAGUGCAUUUGAAGUACAUGGAGUAUAUAAAUGACAUCAAUUAAGUUUUAUUCUCUAUGCUAUCUUUAGAAAUAAAUGGAUACAUUUUGUGCUUGGGGAUGAAAAAAAUUCUUACAUUCACCGUUUUCAUAAGUGCAAUAUUGACAUUUAGUACCGUGUUAUCAUUUGAUAGCUAUGAAAUAUUUCCCUAAUAGUAAUAGGAAAAGAUUAAUAGAGUUAAAUCACCCAAAGUUAUACUUGAGCUUUAUGUAAGUCUAUGGUAAUUAAGACAGUGUGAUAUUAGUGUUAAGAUAGGCAUAUAGAUUAUGGAACCAAAUGGGGAGUUCAUAGACCCACAUAUAUAUAAUCAAUUGAUUUUCAGCAAUGAAGUUAAGCUAAUUCAAUGGCGAGAGGCUAGUGUUUUUUUUUUUUUUUAAGAACAGGUUUCACUCUUGUUGCCCAGGCUGGAGUGCAGUGGCGUAAUCUUGGCUCACCGCAACCUCCACCUCCAGGUUGAAGCGAUUCUCCUGCCUCAGCCUUCCUUAGUAGCUGGGAUUACAGGCAUGCACCACCAUGCCCGGCUAAUUUUAUAUUUUUAGUAGAGACAGGAUUUCUCCAUGUUGGUCAGGCUGGUCUCGAACUCCCGACCUCAGAUGAUCCACCCACCUUGGCCUCCCAAAGUGCUGGGGAUUACAGGCGUGAGCCACUGUGCCUGGCCAGGAGAGGCUAGUGUUUUUAACAAAUGUACUGGAACAACUGAAUAUUCAUAUAGGAAAAAAAAAAUGAACCUUGACCCUUGACCUUUAUCUCAAACUGUACAUUAAAAUAAAUGGAUCAUAGACCUGAAUAUAAUCUUUGUGACCCUGAAUGAGGUACACAUUUCUUAGGUAAACUGAAUAAAAAUUGUUAGACAAAACUGAUAAGUUGGGCUUCAUCAAAAUUUAAAAAAUCAAAUUCCUGUUUCUUGAAAGACAUCAUGAAGAAUAUUUAAAGGCAAGCUGCAGACUGGGAGAAAAUAUUCUGAAUAUGUUUAUAUCUGAUAAAAGACUUGGAUCCAAAAUAUACGAAGAACUCUUGUAAUUCAAUAAUAAGACAGCCCAGUUUAAAAACGGGCAAAAUAUUUGAAUUGAUGCUUCACAAAAUUGGAUUUGAAAAGAUGUUAUUGGUCAUUAGGGAAAUACAAAUUAAAACUAUAGUGAGAUACCACUGCACACACACUAAAAUGGCUACAAUUAAAAACACUGACUGUGGAGCAAUGGUAACUCUCAUGCAUUGCUGAUAAGAGUGCAAAAGAGAAAAGAGUUUUGGCAAUGUCUUUUUAAGUUAAACAUAUGCUUAACAUAUGACCUAGUAAUUCCAUUUUUAGAUAUUUACCCAAGAGAUUAAAAAAUGCCCACAUAAAUUUGUAUGUGACUGUUUGUAGCAGCAUUAUUUAUAAUAGUCGAAAGCUGGAAACAAACCAAGUGUCCAUUAACUGAAUGGAUAAACAAAUUGUGGUAUAUCCAUACAAUGAAAUACUCAGGAAUAAAAGAACUAAUCAUAUAUGCAGCAACAUGGAUGAAUCUCAGAAGUAUUGCUAAGUAAGCCAGACACAUGACAAAGUAAUACUUGAUUCCAUUUAUAUGAAAACUACAGUGACAGAAAGUACUAGUGGUAGCUCAGGGCCAAGGGCUGGGGAGGGUAUUGCAAAAGAACAUGAAGGAAUUUUUUGGAUUGAAGAAAAUAUUCUACAUCUUGAUUGUAGUAGUUGUUGCAUGAGUGUAUACUGUUAUCAGACUCACCAAAAUUUUCAUUUAAGGGGGGUGAAUGUUAUUUUAAGUAAAUGAUACCUUAGUAAAGUUGGUGGAGGAAUGAGACUUGAGAAGCUCCUCAUCCUGCUGAUUUAAAAUUUUGUAAAGCGGUUGUUGAUUCAAAAGGAUAUCUUUGGGAAAAUAUGGUUGCUCCUAGGAUGUGUAAUGCAGGGAAAAAUAUACUCUCUUUGCAGUGUCAUGAUUGAAUUAGCCCUCUGGAGUUGUUAAAGUGCUUUUUUUUUUUUUUUUAAUUACUAGAGUUGCUGUCGUUUAGGUAAAAGGCCAAAAUGAAUUUUAUUAUUUGUUUUUAUUUUAAAUUCUGGGUUUUGACCUUUCUUCCAAUAUAGGCACAGUAUACUUGUUAAUUUGGACUUAGCUAACAUGGAUAACCAUAUUUUCUUCUCUAAUUUCUAUCUCACAGAGUUUAACCCUGAAAUUUUGCUGUGUUUUAUGAAUGAUCCUCUAUACACUGGUCUUUCAAAAAUUGUAGAGAAAAAGUGAAAAACAAUUUAGAGGAAAAUAGGAAAAAAGGGAUUGGAAAAGCCUAUGCUUAAUUAGACUGAGGUUUUAGAAUAGUAAAUAUAUUCUUAGAAGUACUGGUAUUGUCCUGGUUUCUCCCGUAACUUGUGUAUUUUUCUAAUUUGGUAGUCAGCCCUCUCUUAUAUUUCCUACCAUCCUGCUCCCAUUAUCACAAUUUCUUCAUUUGAGAAUGAAGGUGAAGGGAAUUUUAAUGUCUUUUCCUUAAAUAUUUUUGAUGAAUCUCCUUAAAGUGUGCUUUAAAAUCUUUGCUGGAAAGAGAGUCUGCAUUAUCAUCAGUACUCCUAUUAUUUUAUAGUUUUUAAGAUAGACCUUCUUUUACAUUUAAACAUCCCAGAAACUGGGCUAUAUCUGGCAAUAUACCACCUAGAAUUCAAGUUGAGUUCUUCCAGAGAGGAUUUGCUUUCGCUUCUUUCGGUCACCUGGGGAAAAUAUCAACCAUCCUGAUAGUAUAAAUUCAGAGCACAACCUACAUGACUGACUUGUUCAAAUUCUCAGGGAGAGAUUUUCCCCCUCCCUGGACGCAGUACAAAAUGGGAAAUAGAUGUACAGUCAAGGCUGAGAUGUACAGAUUUCUUUGUGGGCCCUUCUGUGUUGUAGAUAUAUUUCUCCCUUAUCCUCAUAUUAUGAGUAUAUCCCUUUUGCUAUCCUAACUUUUUGUGGAAUCUCCUAGGCUGUGACUUGGAAUUUCCCCCCUUUUCUUACUGGUAUAUAAUAUGGGUACAUUUUAUAAUUGAUGGCAUUUUAAAUCUUAAUCAUCUUAAAUUUUGUUCCAUGUAUGUCUCCAUACUGACUUUUCUCUGGAACUUUUAAAUACUGAGUAUAUGAGUGAGUAAAAUGAGUAUUAUAAUUUCAUGUUUUAUUUUAUAAGUGAUAACACAUUUGUUCAGAUUUUUAGUGUGUGUGCUGCCGAAGUGAGCACUGUUCAGAUUUUUAAUGCACAGGAGGCUGUUCUUUUUUUUUUUUUUUGAGACGGAGUCUCACUCUGUUGCCCAGGCUGGAGUGCAGUGGCACGAUCUUGGCUCACUGCAAGCUCUGCCUCCUGGGUUCACGCCAUUCUCCUGCCUUAGACUCCCGAGUAGCUGGGACUACAGCAGGCACCUGCCACCAUGCCCGGCUAAUUUUUUUAUUUUUAGUAGAGACGGGGUUUCACCAUGUCAGCCAGGAUGGUCUCAAUCUCCUGACCUCGUGAUCCACCCGCCUCAGCCUCCCAAAGUGCUGGGAUUACAGGCGUGAGCCACCGCACCCAGCCACUGCUGUUCUCUUGACACAAUCUGAUAAACAAAAUGUAUCCCUCUUGAUGUUCCUCAGAGAAAAUGUUAAAACAAAUUAGUAAGAAGUUACUGGUUAGAAUUUAUGAAAGCAAAACUAAUGCUACUAGAUGUCUGUUGCUUUUAGAAUCUAACCCAAAAUUUCUUGUUGUGUCUGUAUGUCCAUGGUAUUUGAGCUUUGAAUUUUUAAGAAUCCAUUUCAUAAAGUUCUUACCUAUAAUACUUUUUAUAUCAUUAAGCAUACUUUUUACGGAGGAUGGAGACAUAAUGGCAGACUGAGGUCUUCCUAUUACUUUUUUUUAAUAACAGCUUUAUUGAGAUACAAUUCACGUAUCAUUCAAUUCACCCUUUUAAAGCAUACAAUUUGAUCAUUUUAGUAUAUUCACAGAGUUGUGCAACCAAUACCGCUAUCUAAUUUUAGAACAUUUCAUUACCCCCACAAGAAACCCUGUACCCAUUAGCGGAAACUGCCCGUUCCCUCCUCCCCACAGCCUCUGGCAAUGACAAACCCCUAUUAAGUUUCUAGUUUAAGCUUAAUUUUUAGUUCAGUUAAAUAUUGUGUCUGCUAUUACAAGGCCCUAUGUUAGGUGUUGGGAAGAUUAUAAAUCCUGGUCUCAAAGUUUAUAAUCCAAUAAAGAAUAAGAGAACUACCAUAUUUUAUGUCUAUGACAACAUAUAGUAAGUGUCAAAACAGGGAAUUUUGAAGGUUUAAGCCUCUCAUUUGGGUCACAACUUUAUAGAAUUUUAGUUGCUGAUGCAGUUUCUUUCAUUAAGUAGAAAAGUAAUGAGACCCAGAGACAUUACUGUCACAUAGUUCUGUGGCACAACCAGAAUAUUGAUAGUUCCUUGACAAAAUCACUUGAGAUGCAGGGUCUUGAUAAUUAGAGAUAACUGAGGUGGCCCUUUUAGGGAAAAGAAUAUAAACAAAGCCUUAGGGCAUAUUUAGGAAAUAGCAAGUAGCUCACUUUGAUUACUACAGCCAAAGGUGCAUGAUGUGGGACAAUGUAAGAUCAAACUGAUUUUGACAAAAUGAAAGUUUUUGAACUUUAAGAUCCAAUAAUUUGCAAUUUAUUAAUUGGGUAGGUAGUGAGCGAUGACUAAAAGUUCUUAAGAGAGUGAUAUGAUUGGAUCAGGGUUUUAGGACAGUGCUUCUCAAACUGUCUGUGAGGGAGGACCAGUUUAUAAAUAACUUUUUUCCAAUCUGUUUCAAAUGGACACGUUUAUAAAAUAAAAAUGAAUUUCAAGAAAAAUGAAGACACAAAAUGUAAGCCUACCUUUUUUAUUACUACAUUCAACAAACAAAAUUGCUCUGUCAAAUUACUGUAAAAGUUUCUAAAUACUUAAAAUUUCUGUAUGUGUCAUGUCAUGGGUUAGCAACAAAUGUUCAUAAUCCAGCAUUGGCCUGUGGACCAUGCUUUGAGUAGCACUACUUCAAAGCAAUUAAUUUGGCAUUAGUGCGAGGGCAGAGCAAUUGGGAGAUGAUUGCUGGACUAAUGAGGACCUGGACAUGUUGUUAGCACUGUGAAUUGAAUGGAAGAUUGGAUUCCAGAGACGUUUGGUAAUUUAAAUGAAGGCACAUUAGAUGAUUGGAUGUGGAUUUGAAGAAGAGGAAAGAAUCAAAAGAUAGUAACUAGAUUUUAAGCUUGAGUGGGAGAAUGGGAGUGCCCAUAGCAGAAAUAGGAACUAGUUUGGAGAUUGGGUUUUCAACAAAAAAUCCACAUUAUAGCAUUUUCUAUUAAGUAAAAAUAUGCAUAUAUACAGACACAUACUUUUUAGUUCAUAAUUUCAAUUUGCCCUCUCAAAAAGCACUUGUAACUUUUUCUUUUCUUGAUUGUAGCAAAUUUUCAAUGUGUAAUUAUGCAAGCCCAUAAGGAAAACAGAUGCCCAAGAAGAUUUUAUACUUGAAUCCUUAGUCUCAUUUGUUGUUGCACUAACUGUCAUUGGGCACUUGGCCAGGAAAUUGUGACUCCUAGGCAAGGGGAGGAGUUACAGAUAAAGUUCACCAUUGCCAAAGAAAUUCUAUUCCAAAUGGAUUUGUGUGGAGCAACAGUGAUAUCCAAUGACAAGUUAAAUUAAACACAGAGGUGUUUUCUCCAGCACUGUCUCGGAAGAUACAUGCUUUUGAGGGGCCUGAUUCAGGUUAAACUUCUUGAAGUUAAGUCACAAAAAAACUAUACUAGGGACCUUACGAAGAAUUUUGUUAUGUGACUUCAAGAACUAGUUGACUCAGAUAGUUUUACACUUUUCAAAACGGCAACCAGUGACAGAUGAGGGUGUUUGUGAACCGAAGUUUAGCAAUGGAAAAGAUAAAGUGUUUUGGUUUUGAUAUGGAUUAUACCCUUGCUGGAGAGCCAGUGUAACUCCUUCAAGACUGGAGUGACACACACUGCAUCUGCAUCUGCCUCAUUGUACAAGUCCCCAGAGUAUGAGUCCCUUGGUUUUGAGCUUACUGUGGAGAGAUUAGUUUCUAUUGGCUAUCCCCAGGAGUUGCUCAGCUUUGCUUAUGAUUCUACAUUCCCUACCAGGGGACUUGUCUUUGACACACUGUAUGGAAAUCUUUUGAAAGUCGAUGCCUAUGGAAACCUCUUGGUCUGUGCACAUGGAUUUAACUUUAUAAGGGGACCAGAAACUAGAGAACAGUAUCCAAAUAAAUUUAUCCAGCGAGAUGAUACUGAAAGAUUUUACAUUCUGAACACACUAUUCAACCUACCAGAGACCUACCUGUUGGCCUGCCUAGUAGAUUUUUUUACUAAUUGUCCCAGAUAUACCAGUUGUGAAACAGGAUUUAAAGAUGGGGACCUCUUCAUGUCCUACCGGAGUAUGUUCCAGGAUGUAAGAGAUGCUGUUGACUGGGUUCAUUACAAGGGCUCCCUUAAGGAAAAGACAGUUGAAAAUCUUGAGAAGUAUGUAGUCAAAGAUGGAAAACUGCCUUUGCUUCUGAGCCGGAUGAAGGAAGUAGGGAAAGUAUUUCUUGCUACCAACAGUGACUAUAAAUAUACAGAUAAAAUUAUGACUUACCUGUUUGACUUCCCACAUGGCCCCAAGCCUGGGAGCUCCCAUCGACCAUGGCAGUCCUACUUUGACUUGAUCUUGGUGGAUGCACGGAAACCACUCUUUUUUGGAGAAGGCACAGUACUGCGUCAGGUGGAUACUAAAACUGGCAAGCUGAAAAUUGGUACCUACACAGGGCCCCUACAGCAUGGUAUCGUCUACUCAGGAGGUUCUUCUGAUACGAUCUGUGACCUGUUGGGAGCCAAGGGAAAAGACAUUUUGUAUAUUGGAGAUCACAUUUUUGGGGACAUUUUAAAAUCAAAGAAACGGCAAGGGUGGCGAACUUUUUUGGUGAUUCCUGAACUCGCACAGGAGCUACAUGUCUGGACUGACAAGAGUUCACUUUUCGAAGAACUUCAGAGCUUGGAUAUUUUCUUGGCUGAACUCUACAAGCAUCUUGACAGCAGUAGCAAUGAGCGUCCAGACAUCAGUUCCAUCCAGAGACGUAUUAAGAAAGUAACUCAUGACAUGGACAUGUGCUAUGGGAUGAUGGGAAGCCUGUUUCGCAGUGGCUCCCGGCAGACCCUUUUUGCCAGUCAAGUGAUGCGUUAUGCUGACCUCUAUGCAGCAUCUUUCAUCAACCUGCUGUAUUACCCUUUCAGCUACCUCUUCAGGGCUGCCCAUGUCUUGAUGCCUCAUGAAUCAACGGUGGAGCACACACACGUAGAUAUCAAUGAGAUGGAGUCUCCUCUUGCCACCCGGAACCGCACAUCAGUGGAUUUCAAAGACACUGACUACAAGCGGCACCAGCUGACACGGUCAAUUAGUGAGAUUAAACCUCCCAACCUCUUCCCACUGGCCCCCCAGGAAAUUACACACUGCCAUGACGAAGAUGAUGAUGAAGAGGAGGAGGAGGAGGAAGAAUAAGGAGGAAAACCAAAACCCCAAGCACCCAUUAAACAAGUCCUGGCAGGACUCACAGGAACAAACGAGGUCCCUGUUAGGGUUCUACUCGGGGGAGGGAGGGGGCUCCAUGAAAGGUACGUCUGAAAAGUUUCUGAAGAUUUUAUUAUCAUAGAUACUUGUUUUGGUUUUGUGUAUCUGUACUCUCUGCAGAUGGUCCAAAAUUGUAAUGGAGUCUGUAUUAGAAGAAAAUAAGGGUAAAAUCAGGCUGAACUGCAUGUAUAUGGCUCCACUGUGGCUUGUGACACUUUUAAAAUCAUCCGUAUGUCAGUGUAUCUGGAUACACGAGGAAAAGGAAAGAGUCUCAGAGUGGAACAAAGAGUGGGAAGAGGUGAUCUGUAAUGUUACAAAUUGUGCUAUUACUCCAAGGUCCAACUUUUCCAGUGCAUUACAUGGUAUUGUAUAUCAGUGGAGAAAUGUAUUAUUUCCAUGAUCAAAUGUAGUCUCUGUUAAGGUCAAGUUUUCUUUUAUAAGCCUUUAAUUCAUCCUCAGUGACUCUGGCAAGGCUGCUUCUCUAUCACUGGCUUUGCACAGAAGUAUGCUCUACUUGCGUUGCUUUAGGGCAGGAUUCUAUUUUGAGGGAAAAGACAGUAUCCUUAUUACCUUUUGUUUGUUUAAUAGCACAAAUGCUUAUUUGUUAUCCAAAAACAACCUCCUUCUUAUCUGUGAUAAAUCUAUAGAAAGAAUUUAGCUGCAAGUGGACAAAGGAACAAGCCCCCAGAAAAGAAAGGGAAGAACUGCCUUCUUAUACUACAGAACAUGCAUUAGUGUGGGCUAUAUAGCUGUGGCUCAUGCUACCCAAUUCCAGAUUUCUUUGUCCUCUAAGAGUUGAUUGCUGUAUAUUAAAAUUGAACAUCAGAGGAUGGGAAGAGGGCUCUGUAAGCCAGAACCUUACUAAAGUAGAGGGCACAAUCAGUGUGAAUAAAUUCACUUCAGAAUCUCAAGUCAAGGCCAGGCACGGCGGCUCACGCCUGUAAUCCCAGCACUUUGGGAGGCCGAGACAGGCGGAUCACCUGAGGUCGGGAGUUCGAGACCAGCCUUACCAACAUGGAGAAACCCCAUCUCUACUAAAAAUACAAAAUUACCUGGGCGUGGUGGUGCAUGCCUGUAAUCCCAUCAUCUACUCAGGAGGCUGAGGCAGGAGAAUUGCUUGAACCCAGGAGGCGGAGGUUGCAGUGAGCCAGGAUUGUGCCAUUGCACUCCAGCCUGGGCAACAAGAACAAAACUCCAUCUCAAAAAAUAAAAAUCCCAAUCCCAAGUCGAAAUCACCUCUUGUUUUAAACAAGAAUGAAUCAUUACUGUGUAUGUUAGGGUAUUAAAACUGUUUCACCAGUACAGUGAAAGUUGUUUCAACAUUUUAAACAAACAGUGGUUAUAGACUCUUUCUUUAACCAUUGUAUAUUUUCUUCCAUUCUUGUCAUUGGUCAAUAGGGGAGGGUAGAUUAGCUGCUCCAGAAUUCAAUAAAGUGUAAUAUUUCUAACGGUGACUUUGACCUAUUCUGUAGUACAACUGUAAUAGCUAUUGGUCUUCAAGUGGGUUUAGAUUUGGUGACAUCAGUUUGAUAUUCUCUUAAAGGAAAUAAAUAUUCAAGAACUGAUUAUGUUCUAACAUGAUUAUA